AGAACAGCGCAGUUUGCCCUCCGCUCACGCAGAGCCUCUCCGUGGCUUCCGCACCUUGAGCAUUAGGCCAGUUCUCCUCUUCUCUCUAAUCCAUCCGUCACCUCUCCUGUCAUCCGUUUCCAUGCCGUGAGGUCCAUUCACAGAACACAUCCAUGGCUCUCAUGCUCAGUUUGGUUCUGAGUCUCCUCAAGCUGGGAUCAGGGCAGUGGCAGGUGUUUGGGCCAGACAAGCCUGUCCAGGCCUUGGUGGGGGAGGACGCAGCAUUCUCCUGUUUCCUGUCUCCUAAGACCAAUGCAGAGGCCAUGGAAGUGCGGUUCUUCAGGGGCCAGUUCUCUAGCGUGGUCCACCUCUACAGGGACGGGAAGGACCAGCCAUUUAUGCAGAUGCCACAGUAUCAAGGCAGGACAAAACUGGUGAAGGAUUCUAUUGCGGAGGGGCGCAUCUCUCUGAGGCUGGAAAACAUUACUGUGUUGGAUGCUGGCCUCUAUGGGUGCAGGAUUAGUUCCCAGUCUUACUACCAGAAGGCCAUCUGGGAGCUACAGGUGUCAGCACUGGGCUCAGUUCCUCUCAUUUCCAUCACGGGAUAUGUUGAUAGAGACAUCCAGCUACUCUGUCAGUCCUCGGGCUGGUUCCCCCGGCCCACAGCGAAGUGGAAAGGUCCACAAGGACAGGAUUUGUCCACAGACUCCAGGACAAACAGAGACAUGCAUGGCCUGUUUGAUGUGGAGAUCUCUCUGACCGUCCAAGAGAACGCCGGGAGCAUAUCCUGUUCCAUGCGGCAUGCUCAUCUGAGCCGAGAGGUGGAAUCCAGGGUACAGAUAGGAGAUACCUUUUUCGAGCCUAUAUCGUGGCACCUGGCUACCAAAGUACUGGGAAUACUCUGCUGUGGCCUAUUUUUUGGCAUUGUUGGACUGAAGAUUUUCUUCUCCAAAUUCCAGUGUAAGCGAGAGAGAGAAGCAUGGGCCGGUGCCUUAUUCAUGGUUCCAGCAGGGACAGGAUCAGAGAUGCUCCCACAUCCAGCUGCUUCUCUUCUUCUAGUCCUAGCCUCCAGGGGCCCAGGCCCAAAAAAGGAAAAUCCAGGCGGAACUGGACUGGAGAAGAAAGCACGGACAGGCAGAAUUGAGAGACGCCCGGAAACACGCAGUGGAGGUGACUCUGGAUCCAGAGACGGCUCACCCGAAGCUCUGCGUUUCUGAUCUGAAAACUGUAACCCAUAGAAAAGCUCCCCAGGAGGUGCCUCACUCUGAGAAGAGAUUUACAAGGAAGAGUGUGGUGGCUUCUCAGAGUUUCCAAGCAGGGAAACAUUACUGGGAGGUGGACGGAGGACACAAUAAAAGGUGGCGCGUGGGAGUGUGCCGGGAUGAUGUGGACAGGAGGAAGGAGUACGUGACUUUGUCUCCCGAUCAUGGGUACUGGGUCCUCAGACUGAAUGGAGAACAUUUGUAUUUCACAUUAAAUCCCCGUUUUAUCAGCGUCUUCCCCAGGACCCCACCUACAAAAAUAGGGGUCUUCCUGGACUAUGAGUGUGGGACCAUCUCCUUCUUCAACAUAAAUGACCAGUCCCUUAUUUAUACCCUGACAUGUCGGUUUGAAGGCUUAUUGAGGCCCUACAUUGAGUAUCCGUCCUAUAAUGAGCAAAAUGGAACUCCCAUAGUCAUCUGCCCAGUCACCCAGGAAUCAGAGAAAGAGGCCUCUUGGCAAAGGGCCUCUGCAAUCCCAGAGACAAGCAACAGUGAGUCCUCCUCACAGGCAACCACGCCCUUCCUCCCCAGGGGUGAAAUGUAGGAUGAAUCACAUCCCACAUUCUUCUUUAGGGAUAUUAAGGUCUCUCUCCCAGAUCCAAAGUCCCGCAGCAGCCGGCCAAGGUGGCUUCCAGAUGAAGGGGGACUGGCCUGUCCACAUGGGAGUCAGGUGUCAUGGCUGCCCUGAGCUGGGAGGGAAGAAGGCUGACAUUACAUUUAGUUUGCUCUCACUCCAUCUGGCUAAGUGAUCUUGAAAUACCACCUCUCAGGUGAAGAACCGUCAGGAAUUCCCAUCUCACAGGCUGUGGUGUAGAUUAAGUAGACAAGGAAUGUGAAUAAUGCUUAGAUCUUAUUGAUGACAGAGUGUAUCCUAAUGGUUUGUUCAUUAUAUUACACUUUCAGUAA